GAUUUACAGGAAGUUAUGCUCAGUUCCAAUCCAGUUAAACAGUACUUAAAUUGUAGCAGGACAAGCCGCAGACAAAACCCCUCAGCCAGCGAGUUUAAGAAAGAAGGGCUUUAUUCGGCCGGGAUCUUCGGCAAGACUCACGUCUCCAACAACCAAGCUCCCCAACAAUGGACUCUUGUGGCUGACUUCACUCACCAUGCUCACACUGCCUCCUUGUCAGCAGUAGCUGUAAAUAGUCGUUUUGUGGUCACUGGGAGCAAAGAUGAAACAAUUCACAUUUAUGACAUGAAAAAGAAGAUUGAGCAUGGGGCUCUAGUGCAUCACAGUGGUACAAUAACUUGCCUGAAAUUCUAUGGCAACAGGCAUUUAAUCAGUGGAGCGGAAGAUGGACUCAUCUGUAUCUGGGAUGCAAAGAAAUGGGAAUGCCUGAAGUCAAUUAAAGCUCACAAAGGACAGGUGACCUUCCUUUCUAUUCACCCAUCUGGCAAGUUGGCCCUGUCGGUUGGUACAGAUAAAACUUUAAGAACGUGGAAUCUUGUAGAAGGAAGAUCAGCAUUCAUAAAAAAUAUAAAACAAAAUGCUCACAUAGUAGAAUGGUCCCCAAGAGGAGAGCAGUAUGUAGUUAUCAUACAGAAUAAAAUAGACAUCUAUCAGCUUGACACUGCAUCCAUUAGUGGCACCAUCACAAAUGAAAAGAGAAUUUCCUCUGUUAAAUUUCUUUCAGAGUCUGUCCUUGCAGUGGCUGGAGAUGAAGAAGUUAUAAGGUUUUUUGACUGUGAUUCACUAGUGUGCCUCUGCGAAUUUAAAGCUCAUGAAAACAGGGUAAAGGACAUGUUCAGUUUUGAAAUUCCAGAGCAUCAUGUUAUUGUUUCAGCAUCGAGUGAUGGUUUCAUCAAAAUGUGGAAGCUUAAGCAGGAUAAGAAAGUUCCCCCAUCUUUACUCUGUGAAAUAAACACUAAUGCCAGGCUGACGUGUCUUGGAGUGUGGCUAGACAAAGUGGCAGACAUGAAAGAAAGCCUUCCUCCAGCUGCAGAGCCUUCUCCUGUAAGUAAAGAACAGUCCAAAAUUGGCAAAAAGGAGCCUGGUGACACAGUGCACAAAGAAGAAAAGCGGUCAAAACCUAACACAAAGAAACGCGGUUUAACAGGUGACAGUAAGAAAGCAACAAAAGAAAGUGGCCUGAUAUCAACCAAGAAGAGGAAAAUGGUAGAAAUGUUGGAAAAGAAGAGGAAAAAGAAGAAAAUAAAAACAAUGCAGUGAAUCACAGAUGUCUCCUGAAAGAACUCUUUUAGAUGAAAUCAUUCUACUCAAAUGUACCUUAAUUUUUUUUUUUUCCCUGAGUAAAAGCAAGAAAUUUCUUCCUUUGGAAAAAAUAUAUAUAUUAAAAAACCACUUUUAGAUGGUUUUUUUUAAAAAAAAAAAAAAAACUGGUAAAAUUACUUUUGGCAGACAGUGUUUUAUGAAUUAUGUAUCAUGUUGAUAUAUAAUAUGUUAAUGUGUCAUGUAAUUUUUACUUUGUACAAAGCAAAUAAAGAUCUUUCUCAAAAUAUACUGUAAAAUAAUAUAAAAUAUUGAACACAUUCUUUAUCA